UUUAUAACGAUGUUGGUGCAUUUUUUGAAGAAGGGAUGUGGCUACGAUAUAACUUUCAGGCACCAGCAACAAAUGCCAGAGACUCCAGCAGCAGAGUAGACAACGCUCCCGACCAGCAGAACUCCCACCCGGACCUGGCACAGGAGGAGAUCCGCUUCAGCUUCAGCACCACCAAGGCGCCCUGCAUUCUCCUCUACAUCAGCUCCUUCACCACAGACUUCUUGGCAGUCCUCGUCAAACCCACUGGAAGCUUACAGAUUCGAUACAACCUGGGUGGCACCCGAGAGCCAUACAAUAUUGACGUAGACCACAGGAACAUGGCCAAUGGACAGCCCCACAGUGUCAACAUCACCCGCCACGAGAAGACCAUCUUUCUCAAGCUCGAUCAUUAUCCUUCUGUGAGUUACCAUCUGCCAAGUUCAUCCGACACCCUCUUCAAUUCUCCCAAGUCGCUCUUUCUGGGAAAAGUUAUAGAAACAGGGAAAAUUGACCAAGAGAUUCACAAAUACAACACCCCAGGAUUCACUGGUUGCCUCUCCAGAGUCCAGUUCAACCAGAUCGCCCCUCUCAAGGCCGCCUUGAGGCAGACAAACGCCUCGGCUCACGUCCACAUCCAGGGCGAGCUGGUGGAGUCCAACUGCGGGGCCUCGCCGCUGACCCUCUCCCCCAUGUCGUCCGCCACCGACCCCUGGCACCUGGAUCACCUGGAUUCAGCCAGUGCAGAUUUUCCAUAUAAUCCAGGACAAGGCCAAGCUAUAAGAAAUGGAGUCAACAGAAACUCGGCUAUCAUUGGAGGCGUCAUUGCUGUGGUGAUUUUCACCAUCCUGUGCACCCUGGUCUUCCUGAUCCGGUACAUGUUCCGCCACAAGGGCACCUACCAUACCAACGAAGCAAAGGGGGCGGAGUCGGCAGAGAGCGCGGACGCCGCCAUCAUGAACAACGACCCCAACUUCACAGAGACCAUUGAUGAAAGCAAAAAGGAAUGGCUCAUUUGAGGGGUGGCUACUUGGCUAUGGGAUAGGGAGGAGGGAAUUACUAGGGAGGAGAGAAAGGGACAAAAGCACCCUGCUUCAUACUCUUGAGCACAUCCUUAAAAUAUCAGCACAAGUUGGGGGAGGCAGGCAAUGGAAUAUAAUGGAAUAUUCUUGAGACUGAUCACAAAAAAAAAAACCUUUUUAAUAUUUCUUUAUAGCUGAGUUUUCCCUUCUGUAUCAAAACAAAAUAAUACAAAAAAUGCUUUUAGAGUUUAAGCAAUGGUUGAAAUUUGUAGGUAAUAUCUGUCUUAUUUUGUGUGUGUUUAGAGGUGUUCUAAAGACCCGUGGUAACAGGGCAAGUUUUCUACGUUUUUAAGAGCCCUUAGAACGUGGGUAUUUUUUUUCUUGAGAAAAGCUAAUGCACCUACAGAUGGCCCCCAACAUUCUCUUCCUUUUGCUUCUAGUCAACCUUAAUGGGCUGUUACAGAAACUAGUUCGUGUUUAUAUACUAUUUCCUUUGAUGUCCUAUAAGUCGGAAAAGAAAGGGGCAAAGAGAACCUAUUAUUUGCCAGUUUUUAAGCAGAGCUCAAUCUAUGCCAGCUCUCUGGCAUCUGGGGUUCCUGACUGAUACCAGCAGUUGAAGGAAGAGAGUGCAUGGCACCUGGUGUGUAACGACACAAUCAGCACAACUGGAGAGAGGCAUUAAAGAACCAGGGAAGGUAGUUUGAUUUUUCAUUGAAUUCUACAAGCUAAUAUUGUUCCACGUAUGUAGUCUUAGACCAAUAGCUGUAACUAUCAGCUGCAAUACCAUGGUGACCAGCUGUUACAAAAGAUUUUUUCCUGUUUUAUCUGAAACAUACUGGAUUUAUAUAUGUAUAAGCGCCUCAAUGGGGAAUUAGAGCCAGAUGUUAUGAUUUGUUUGCUCUUUUUCUUUUAUAGUUUAGUUAUAGCAAAAAUAUGGAUAAUUUCUAGUGAAUGCAUAAAUUAGGUUGCGUUUCUUAUUUUGCUUUAAAUCUCUGGUAGUUUUUCCACCCCUGUGACACAAUCCUAAUAGACAGUGUCCUGUAAAUGGACACAACACAAUAAAGUCAAGUUAUUAUUGCUGUUACUCUGGAUGAUAUGGAAAACACUGCCAUAUUUUAAAUCAACUACUCCACGUGUUUUUCCAUCCAAUCACACUGCUGUGAUUCAGGGAUCUUUCUUCUAAGACGGACACAUUUGAACCUCAGGUUCAUCACAAACCUGGUACCUGUUGCUUCCCAGAGGAUGGAGAAGUGUAGUUAAUCACACCUCUUAGUUUAAUCUGAAAUCUUGACCCAGUUAUUUAACAAAUAAAUACCUCAUUGAUUAUAUUUAAAAGUAAUACACUUCCUGUAAACAAAUGGGGACAAUGCAUCCAAAAAAUCUUUUUAAACAGAUUACACAAAAAUUAUUUCCAGAAAGGCUACCAUUUAUCAUCAUUAUAUUUCAAGCCUCUUAUACUUAAUAAGCACUUUCUAAAAAGUCUUGAGAUCCCACCAUUCUGAGGAAUUCAAUAUGAUCACUUUUUCCUUCUUUGCCUGGGAGAGGUUAAGAGGAGGUUUCGAAGGUAUAGAUGCUAUUGUUCUGAUGGCCCGGCUGAAUAAAAUGGAAAUUCUAGUUUGUUAGAAUUAUGCAUUCUUUUUCAAGAUUCUCAGUGUGCCUAACUUAUUGGAGCACAUCAGUUUCUUGGGUAAUGGAAAACAUUACCUAGAGUUGCCAGUGGCACAUUACACCAGUACAGAGCACAUUCCAAAGGAGACAUUGGACCAGUUAAUUCCCAUACAAGUCAAGGUAACAGAACAAAAGGGAAUCCUGAUGCCCUUUUACCAUUGCUGGUUGAGCUCAGGCACUGUCAUGGACACCCUUAAUUUUAAAAGGUUUUAAUCAUUCUUCUAUAAAAUACAUUUAAAAUGGAAAAAUACUUAAUAUCACUAAAUAUCAGAACAAUGUAACAUUUACAAAUGACAUAUUGAAAGCAAAGGCUGUUUUAUUUAGCCAAGAUGAUUACCAUUAGGAGUUACUUUAUGUAUUGUUGAAAGCAAAUUUUAAACAUGAUGUUUUAGAAGUGUUUCUGAUUUUUAAACCUGGUUUACAGGUAUUACUUCUGCACUUACCAAAUAAUGCCAGAUGGAAAUUUAUUAUUUCUUGCAAUUCCCAUGAUAGCUCUGUUCUUUAUGCAUUGUCUCAACACUUUCCCUUUUUUCCCAAAAUGAGUAGAGAAUUAAAGCCACCCAAAACAGCUUCUGCUACUAAAAUGUUCUCAUCCUUUCUCCUCCCUCUCCUUUUCCUGCCACAAAAGGUGAAAAAUGAGAUCCAAUCCUCUCACCAAAAUUUCAAACCUAGGACACUGGAAUGACUGCAGGGAUCAGUGGUUCUCCCAUAUCACCAUCAAUUAAGACAUAUAGGACACUGUCUUCCUUCAAGAGGGUUACAAUGUGGCCAUCAGACAGGAAACCAAACGGUGGAUAAAGUAUUAAGUAACUAAGUGCCAAAUAAAUGCUGGAAAUCUUGACCUCUCCUUGGGAUUAUGGGUGUAACAAAAAUCCCUACAUCUGUUUAUGAAGGCCAUAUUCAGUACAUUUUAAAUGGUAAAUAAUCUGUUUAUGUGAAGAAAAAGAAUUAAGUCUUUCUUCCAACUCUCUCCUUGGAUAGCCUAGCACAGUGCAGCCUCCAUAACCAUGACAUUCCCGCCCAAGCUCUCAGUGCCUAAUCCUGCUUUGUCAUUCACAUCUCACAAAAUCUUGACAUCUUACAUUCCAAUACAUUAUCAAGCAAGCACAAGUAUGCUGGUAGUAGCCUCUUUAAAUAAUAUGUAUAGACAACAACAACGACAAAAAAUAGACUGUUUUAAAGUUUCAGGGAAAGUUGGUGGCUGAUUUAAAGUUGUGCAGGAAACAUCUUCUGUGUAUGAAGCAAAUGUCGAUGUUUUGAAAAAAGCUAGGAGAUGACUUUGAAUGAAUGCAAGGUUAGUGAGAUCCUAAGCUCUCAAAAUAGCAUAUUCCCUAGAGCUCAAGAAAGCUGGUCCAGGAGGUUGAAAAAGCUAUUUUGUUGUUAAAUUAUUUUCUGGCCCUUCUUAAUAUUUAAAAAUGUAUUUCCCCUUGUGGCUUUCAACCACCUGCUCAAAAAAAGAGACUUGUUACAUGAAAGUUUUCAUUAAAGAGCUGAAAACAAGAAUUUAGAGAGCCAUUCCUAGAAAAUGUCCUACUGCCCUGCAUUUGACAAACAAGCAUCCUUUACUAACAAGAGCAGGAAUUCAGAGGCACAAGAAAAAGCAUUGGCAUGAGCCAAAGAGUCUGUCUUAAUGUUACUUUUGAAAAUCUGCUGAGCGGCCACCAUAUGCAGGCUGAGAGCUGGGCACAGGCGAAGCCAUUGGAAGCACUUCAGGAACAAGCACACAGCUGUGGGACUUGAACAUGCAAGUGUUCAGGUUGUGUCAAGAAGCUUUUCUUUCCUUCUAUGAUGGAAUCUGUUCUUUUCUAUCCUACUUUUUUCUCUCUUCCUCUCCUCACCACAUUAUACCCUGCUCUUACGCAGUAAACGUUUUAAUGGCCCGUUUAUGUCUCAUGCCUCCAAACAACACUGAAUUUGAAACCCCCCAUUUUUUCUUUUCACCACCCUGUUGAGCAAUUUUCCCAAAAAAAGGGCAGCAAUUAUUAAAUUGAAUUCAAGUAAGCCAGCCAAAGAUAGGUCCUAAAUUGCUAGUCCCAGUAGAACCACCUGAUCCUAAACCAGUGCGAAACAAACAGUAACAAUGUCCCCAGCUGACUUCAGCUAAGAACCAAUGGCUCCUACCCCCGCCCCGCUUUUUUUUGUUGUUUUUUGUUUUGUUUUGAGACGGAGUCUUGCUCUGUCCCCCAGGCUGGAGUGCACUGGCGCAAUCUCGGGCUCACUGCAACCUCCUCCUCCUCCCACAUUGAGGCGAUUCUCCUGCCUCAGCCUCCCAAGUAGCUGGGAUUACAGGCACCCGCCAUCACACCCAGCUAAUUUUUUUUUUUUUUUGUAUUAUUAGUAGAAGCCAGGUUUCACCAUGUUGGCCAGGGUGGUCUCGAACUCCUGACCUCAAGUGAUCCGUCCACCUCGGCCUUGCAAAUUGCUGGGAUUACAGGUGUGAGCCACCGUGCCGAGCCAGCCCCAUUUUUUAAAUGAUGUUUUGGUUAAGAGUGGACCAUGAGAAUUAGCUGACAGCAUCCCCUUUCUCUCUCCCUGCCUUGGUGGGACCCUCCCUGUGUGACCUUGGUCAAGUCCUCGAACUUUUGUCCCGUAUUUAAGAUGGAGCUGUUUUACCUACUUCAUAAGACAGUUGCGAGGUGCCAUUGAUUCUUGACUGCAAAAUACCUUGAAACCCUUAUAUAAAGACUGAAGUCAACGGAGCCUAGUGAAAGACUUACUUUGUGGCUUGUGGUUGAAAGUCACAUCAAAAGACAAAUGUGGCCACGUUCAGGAAUUGGAGACUUACUGGCAUGGCUCUACAGCUGCUCAGUUAUUAAUCAUGCAGACUAACCUGUCAACACUGGGAGAUGCAACAUAGCAAAAGGACAGAGAAAUUAGAAUUUUUUGUGCAGAAAGCCCUAAAUUCCCACCUGAAUGUAACUUACAGCUCCCUUACCUACUCUCACACAUGCCCUCAAACAUGCUAGAUUGGCUUAUACAUAGGCCAACACAAAAUACAAACGUGACGUGUUCAUGUAGCCUAGUGGCUAUAUGCCUAUUCUCCAUGUACCCUGCAUGGUAGUGCUGCAAACUUUAAAGUACAUUUCUUUCACAGCAGUAUUUUUUUUCAUAAGUGGCAUAUAAAUGUCAUUCAAUGAAAUGGGGAAAUCACGUUGAGAAGUUGGUCUGUCAUCUCCCAUUGAGCAAAGACUGGCAGGAGAUAAUAAAAAUAAAUAUGGGCACACAUGUAUUAAUAUACAGCACGCAUUUACAAGUUUAUUUUCCAGAUAAAAUUGUGCUAUAAGAACAGCUCUACCAAGACAGUCUGCACCAUUUCCAAGUCUCAGUUAAUUUACAGCAACUGCUGCUUUCGGAGAUGGCUGUGAAAAUAUGGAAGUUCCUCUCAAGUAGGCCAAGAAACAGUUCUAGAUUUUACUAAGUUUUAUUUUGUCAGGUUUUUUAAAUUUUUUCAGUGAGCGUGGUGACUGCAGAGGUUAGUGCUGUGAAAAGCUGGGCUAAAUAUUCUUUCUGUAAAGUCAAACAGGAUUCCAUCCCCUGUGAAAUAACACAAAAUUUCACUCUCUAAAAGCAACAGCAUGUAAACUAGAAUGAAAGAAGGAAAUUAUGUACGUAUGCCUAAUAUUCUUUGUGAAUGUCUUUCAUUUAACUAAAAUUAUAUUAGAAACCAGAUUGAUAAAUAAAAAAUUCAAAGUAGUUUUAAUUAUCCUAAAA